AGUUUCCGCCGCGUUUAUGGCCGCGUUAAGUCUGAGUGCCGCUUUGAGUUGUUGAAUGAAGUGAACUUCAUUUGUCAGCGUUCGGUUCAUGAACUGGAAUGUAAGAGGCACCAGAGGAUUCCUGCUCUGUCCCCUGGUUUGCGGCUUGCGACGUUGGACAUCCCCGGAUUGUUGUUUAAUAGAGAAAACUCACCUGCCUUCUUGCUUUUAAGUAGCCCCAAAAGCAGAACCUUGAUUUGUCUGUAAGGAAGAAACACAAACCUUUUAAAAAGUUCCACUUCGACUCUGCACCGCCGACCCCCAAUCUCUUUAAUUUUGCCAUAGAAGAGGGGUUUUUUCAACAUCUCUCUCACUAUCUGGUGCUGAUCUCACUGCAUAAUGACUUUCUAUUUGUUUGGUAUUCGAAGCUUUCCGAAGCUUUGGAAGAGCCCAUACCUUGGGCUAGGCCCAGGGCACUCUUAUGUCUCGCUGUUUCUGGCAGACCGCUGUGGCAUCAGGAACCAGCAGAGGUUGUUUUCUCUUAAAACAAUGUCUCCACAGAAUACCAAAGCAACGAAUCUGAUUGCCAAGGCCAGAUAUCUCAGGAAAGAUGAGGGCAGUAAUAAGCAAGUUUAUUCUGUUCCUCAUUUUUUUUUAGCUGGAGCAGCUAAGGAGAGAUCACAGAUGAAUUCUCAAACUGAAGAUCAUGCCUUGGCACCUGUGAGGAACACUAUUCAACUCCCAACACAACCUUUGAAUUCAGAGGAGUGGGAUAAACUUAAGGAAGAUUUAAAAGAAAACACCGGAAAGACCAGUUUCGAAAGUUGGAUCAUUUCACAGAUGGCUGGCUGUCAUAGCUCUAUAGAUGUGGCUAAAUCUCUGCUGGCAUGGGUAGCAGCCAAAAAUAAUGGUAUUGUAAGUUACGAUUUACUGGUCAAGUAUUUGUAUCUCUGUGUCUUUCAUAUGCAGACAUCUGAAGUUAUUGAUGUCUUUGAAAUUAUGAAAGCCAGAUAUAAGACUUUAGAACCUAGAGGUUACAGUCUUCUCAUCCGGGGAUUGAUCCAUUCAGACAGAUGGAGAGAAGCAUUGUUGCUGUUAGAGGACAUCAAAAAAGUUAUAACUCCUUCAAAAAAGAACUAUAAUGACUGUAUCCAGGGAGCUCUCCUUCAUCAAGAUGUAAACACAGCUUGGAAUUUAUAUCAGGAAUUGCUAGGUCAUGAUAUUGUUCCUAUGUUGGAAACUUUAAAAGCUUUCUUUGAUUUUGGAAAAGACAUAAAGGAUGAUAACUAUUCAAAUAAACUACUAGAUAUUCUUUCAUAUCUAAGAAAUAAUCAGCUGUAUCCAGGGGAGUCAUUUGCACACAGUAUAAAAACAUGGUUUGAGAGUGUUCCUGGAAAACAAUGGAAAGGACAAUUCACCACAGUCCGAAAAAGUGGCCAGUGUUCGGGCUGUGGAAAAACCAUAGAGUCUAUUCAGCUGAGUCCAGAAGAAUAUGAAUGUCUUAAGGGAAAAAUCAUGAGGGAUGUGAUAGAUGGAGGUGACCAGUACAGAAAGACAACACCUCAGGAACUUAAGAGAUUUGAGAACUUCAUAAAAUCUCGUCCUCCUUUUGAUGUUGUCAUUGAUGGUCUCAAUGUUGCCAAAAUGUUUCCUAAAGUUCGUGAAUCUCAACUUCUCUUGAAUGUCGUCUCUCAACUAGCCAAACGGAAUCUGCGACUGCUGGUCCUAGGCCGGAAGCACAUGCUAAGACGGAGUUCCCAGUGGAGUCGGGAUGAGAUGGAAGAGGUGCAAAAGCAAGCCAGCUGUUUUUUUGCUGAUGACAUCUCGGAGGAUGAUCCAUUCCUUCUGUAUGCCACACUGCACUCCGGGAAUCACUGCAGGUUUAUCACAAGAGACCUGAUGCGGGACCACAAGGCCUGUCUGCCUGAUGCCAAGACCCAACGCCUGUUUUUUAAGUGGCAGCAGGGACAUCAGCUGGCAAUUGUAAAUAGGUUUCCAGGAUCAAAACUAACCUUUCAGCGUAUUCUCAGCUAUGACACAGUGGUGCAAACAACUGGAGACUCGUGGCACAUACCAUAUGAUGAAGACUUGGUAGAAAGAUGUUCCUGUGAAGUACCAACCAAAUGGCUUUGCCUCCACCAAAAGACAUAGAGAUUCUUACCUCUAUGCUAAGUUUGUGUUUGGGUACCCUCUAGGUUGGCAUCAGAGGCUCUUGAGCUGGUGUUUGUUUAGGGCAUUGCCUCUGUCCUGAAGAUAAAAGGAUUCUAUUAACAGCAUUGACAUUGAUUUUUUAAUGAAAUGAGAUAUAUCUUUUCAUAACCAGCUGCGUUUUUUUCCCCUAACAUUUGUUUUUGGAGGCUUAUCAAGAGUUGGAGAACUUAGUGUAGAGCAAAACCUGCAUUUCUCCUACUGGGCCAGCUAUUCCACUUAGCUUGGGUGACUAAUAGUGCUUUUGGUAUCCAUUUUUUGCUACUUCUGACCUUGCCUUCCAGGCCUACCAAUAGCAGAAUCAAUCCAUCUGUCCCUGAGAUACUCAUGUUGUUUCAAAUGCCUCCUCCCAUUUCUGGCAUAGUCUCAUUCUCUGUAUGUUAUGCCCUAUCCACAUGGAAUCAUUUAUCGUCCUCUGUAAUAAACUGGCCAAGAUACUAAAGGCUUACUAUUCAUAGCAGUUUUUAAUUACUUAUCAUCCAAUUAUUUGGAUUGGAGAAGAGGGGGCAUUCACUCCUCUUUUUCUUAUUUUUUUUGGAAAUAGAGUCUCAACUUACUCUGUCGCCAGGGCUGGAGUGCAGUGACGUGAUCACAGUUCACUGCAGCCUCAAACUCCCAGGCUCAAGCAAUCUUCCUACCUCAGCCCUCCUGAGUAAUUGGGACUACAGGCAUGUAUCACCAGGCUUGGCUAAUUUUUUUUUUUUUUUUUGUAGAGAUGGCUGUCUCACUCUGUUGACAAGACUAGUCUCCAACCCCUGGCCUCAGUCGAUCCCCAGCAAUUUGGGAGAUUGAAGCGAGAGAAUCACUUGAGUCUAGGAGUUCAAGACCAGCCUAGGCAACAUAGUAAGAUCUCAUUUCUACAAAAAAUUUAAAAAUUAGCCAGGCAUGGUAGUUUGCACACAUAGUCCCAGCUACUUUGGGGGCUGAGGUAGGAGGAUUGCUUGAGCCUCAGAGGUCAAGGCUGCAAUGAGCCAACGUUGCACCACUGCACUCUAGCCUGGGUGACAGAGCGAGACCUUGUCUCAAAACAAAACAAAGUGCUGGAAUUGCAGACUUGAGCCACAGUGCCCAGCCUCACUUCUCUAGACUAUGAUGGUUUUUUCUUCAUUCUAUAAUCUCUUUUCCAAAUUGGUUCAACAUUUUGUGAACACUAUUAAUUUCAUCAUUCAGUAUAUGUGGGCUUUCUAAAAUAUGCCAAUUUUUUUCCACUUAAUCAAGUUUGACUUAAUUUAACAAAGUGAUUAUAUUUUAAUAGUUACAUUUCUGUUUUUUCCACUCACUAGCCAGCUUACAGUUUAUUAGCCCUUGAUUUCAGCUGAAAAUAUUCAUGUCUGCACCCCUUCAUGAUAGUUCUUUCUUUACGUAUACAUACUGUAUUCAAUAUGCAAGAACAGGCAAAAACUACUCUAUUGUGAUAAAAAUCAGAAUAGUAAUUGCCUGAGGAAAGGGAUAUGAGAGAACUUGAGAGAACUUUCUCGGGGUGAUGGAAAGUUUCUUAUAUUGAUUUGGGUAAUAGUAACAUAGCUAUAUGUAUAUAUUAGUUAAAAUUCCUCACACUAAACAUUUUAAAUUGAUAUAUUUACAUUUAUGACAAUAUACCUCAAAGUAAGUUAGGGUAAGAAAAGAUAAUUACUUACAUGAAAUAAACAAUGACCUCUUUUAUAUCAAACCAUAUACAUGUGUAUAAUUAGGGUAUGUAUUAUGCACAGAGAAACAAUUUAGGAAAAUCCAAGGAGGGGACGUUUUAUCUUCUUACCUAUUUACUGAAUGCAACAUUACUGCACACCAAGACAAAAGAGCUCUCCAGGAAAACAUUGGAUAUAUUGAGAGCAUUAAAAGAUACUGCAAAAGCUCUAAUAAAUUCAGUCUGCUUAUUUUCCAAAUUUCAUAAACUACAUACUUAGGAAACUGUGCUUUCAGUGAGCUAAACUUCUUUUUUUAAGUAACUAUCAUAGUUUUAAGAAAAACAUUUUAAGAAGACAAAAAGUAUUUAUUAAGCCCAUCUAAAAGGCUAAUGCAAAUUCCCAAAAAAGGAGCACAUAGAGAUAGAGGAGGAGGCCGAAGUGGUGGCUCAUACCUGUUAAUUCCAGCACUUUGGGAGGCCAAGACAGGAGGAUCACUUUAGGCCCAGAGUUGGAGACCAACCUGGGCAACAUAGCAAGACCCUGUCUCUUAAAAAAAAAAAAAAAAGACGGGAGAAGCUACAAGAAGAAAACUAGAACUUUAGAGCAGGAGUAACCUUAGAGCAUGUAAAGUCCAUUUUGGAGAUGAGGAACAGACCCAGGAAGAUGACCUGGCUUCCCUGAAUCCCACGGCUAGUUAGUGCAGACAUUUCAGCCAUAACCCAGCUCUUCUAAUUCCCAAAUACUCUUUCUUCUACUGGCACAUAGAGAUGGGGGAGGAGUCAGGGCAUGGUGGCCCACACCUACAGUUCCAGCACUUUGGGAGGCCAAAUGGGAGAAUUGCUUGAAGCCAGGAGUUGGAGACCAGCCUAGGCAACACAGGGAGACCCGUGUCGACAAAAAAUUUAAAAAUUAGCUGGGCAUGGUAGCACAUGCCUGUGGUCCCAGCUACUCAGAAGGCUGAGGUGGGAGGAUCACUUGAGCCCCAGAGGUCAAGGCUACAGUGAGCUAUGAUCAUGCUACUACACUCCAGCCUAGGUGACAGAGUGAGACCCUGUCUCAAAGGGAGGGAGGUAAGAAUGAGAAGAAGGAACAGGGGUGUACCUCUUUUAAGGGCCCAAGUAUCCUGAAUGGCUCAGCAGUAUAGAACAUUGUGGUAGAGAAAUUACAUUUUAAAAUAACUCUAAUACUGUUUAGAAACAAAACCCUAACUUCUGCUUGAGAUAAACUGAAGUGCAUCUGUCCCUUGUCCAGGAGUGGGGAACCAUUGUAGGGUUGCUCAGCAUAAGUCAUACUGCCACGGUGACCUUGAGGAGUGCAGGGAUUCCCUGAAGGAAGCAGCUGGUACCAGACACUUAGGCUGCCCAUUUGUGUUCUGAUCAUUUGAGUGAAAAAAAGGUACCUGUCAAGCAAGCUCCUGGACACCACAAGAAGGAGGAAUUAUUUUAAAAGCUGUACUCUUAAAUUGUUAGUAUCUUUAAAAUCAGUUGUGAACAAUGAAGGAUUUGAAAGAGCAUUGACUUUGCCACUUAAAAGUAUUUCUAAAAUACUUUGUGCUUCCCCCUUGCAUUCUGAAUUUAUACACUUUUCCUCCUGCUGUUCUCAGACCCAGUGGAAAGAAAAUCUCAAGGAAGAAGGCUGAGUUUAUUCUCUCAGGGCUCUGUUGGGUCUACCUCAUCUGAGGUGGCUUAUUCUUCAUAGGAAAUUAAUUUUUCUUCUCAAGUAUGCACUUAAAUAUAAUUACUGCUUCCUUGGUCCUCUAGCAGAUUUCUCACUUUUAUUUAUUUUUUUUUUUGAGACAGAGUCUUGAUCUUUUUUCAUCUAGGCUGGAGUGCAAUGGUUUGAUCUCAGUUCACUGCAACCUCUGCCUCCUGGGUUCAAGCAAUUCUCAUGCCUCUGCCUCUCGGGCAGCUGGAAUUACAGGCAUGCGCCAUGACGCCUGGCUAAUUUUUGCAUUUUUAGUAGAGACGGGUUUUCACCAUGUUGCCCCGGUUGCUCUCAAACUCCUGACCUCAGGUGAUCCACCCACCUCAGCCUCCCAAAGUGCUGGGAUUACAGGUGUGAGUCACCCCGCACAGCCUGAAAUGAGGCAUCUCUAUCUAUAGUCCAGCAGCCCUACAGGAGGCAGGAGGGGAGCAAGAAUAAGAAAGGAAAUUUGUAAAAGGCACUUAGGAGUGAGCAGAAAGGAAAUAGGACCAGCUUUUACCUGCCCAGUCCUGGCCAGUGACAAGCAGUCUGCUUGAGUCUGUGCUAAAUAAACAAAGGAAGUUCCAUUUAGAGCUCUACAGAGGGGAAGCCAUAGAAAUUAACAGGAUGAAAAUACAAGAGACAGGAACACAGAUGAAUAAAUGUAAUAAAAUUUGAGAAAUAAUCUUUA